GUUUCAUCCCUCAGCCUCAGGCUGAGCCGGACCGAGCCGAGAGGACCCGAGUGGGGCCGAGGCCAGUAGCCCCGGGGCCCUGAGCAGAGGCCGUAGCUUGCGCCGCACCCGCGGCCAGGCGGAGCCAAAGAUGCCGGCCUCUGCUGCGCGGCCCCGCCCGGGUCCCGGGCAGCCUACAGCCUCGCCCUUCCCGCUACUGCUGCUGGCGGUGCUGAGCGGCCCGGUAUCCGGCCGCGUCCCCCGCUCGGUGCCCAGAACCUCGCUUCCAAUCUCUGAGGCUGACUCCUGUCUCACCCGGUUCGCAGUCCCUCACACAUACAAUUACUCUGUUCUCCUUGUGGAUCCUGCCUCCCACACACUUUAUGUUGGCGCCCGGGACACCAUCUUCGCUUUAUCCCUGCCCUUCUCAGGGGAGAGACCCCGCAGGAUUGACUGGAUGGUUCCUGAGGCUCACAGACAGAACUGUAGGAAGAAAGGCAAGAAAGAGGACGAAUGUCACAAUUUUGUCCAGAUUCUCGCCAUUGCCAAUGCCUCUCACCUCCUCACUUGUGGCACCUUCGCUUUUGAUCCGAAGUGCGGGGUUAUUGAUGUGUCCAGGUUCCAGCAGGUUGAAAGACUUGAGAGUGGCCGGGGGAAAUGUCCUUUUGAGCCAGCUCAGCGGUCAGCAGCUGUAAUGGCUGGGGGGGUCCUCUAUGCUGCCACUGUGAAAAACUACCUGGGGACGGAGCCAAUUAUCACCAGAGCAGUGGGUCGUGCCGAGGACUGGAUUCGGACAGAUACCUUGCCUUCCUGGCUGAACGCCCCAGCCUUUGUCGCAGCCGUGGCCUUGAGCCCAGCCGAAUGGGGGGAUGAAGAUGGAGACGACGAAAUCUACUUCUUCUUUACGGAGACUUCCCGAGCAUUUGACUCAUACGAGCGCAUUAAAGUCCCACGGGUGGCCCGUGUGUGUGCGGGGGACCUCGGGGGCCGGAAGACCCUCCAGCAGAGAUGGACGACGUUUUUGAAAGCUGACCUGCUCUGUCCAGGGCCUGAGCAUGGCCGGGCCUCCAGUGUCCUGCAGGAUGUUGCUGUGCUUCGACCUGAGCUUGGGGCAGGGACUCCCAUCUUUUAUGGCAUCUUUUCUUCCCAGUGGGAGGGGGCUACUAUCUCUGCUGUCUGUGCCUUCCGACCACAAGACAUUCGGACAGUGCUGAAUGGUCCCUUCAGAGAACUAAAACAUGACUGCAACAGAGGACUGCCUGUCGUGGACAAUGAUGUGCCCCAGCCCAGACCUGGAGAGUGCAUCACCAACAACAUGAAGCUCCGGCACUUUGGCUCAUCUCUCUCCCUGCCUGACCGCGUACUCACCUUCAUCCGGGACCACCCACUCAUGGACAGGCCAGUGUUUCCAGCUGAUGGCCACCCCCUGCUGGUCACUACAGAUACAGCCUAUCUCAGAGUCGUGGCCCACAGGGUGACCAGCCUCUCAGGGAAAGAGUAUGAUGUGCUCUACCUGGGGACAGAGGAUGGACACCUCCACCGAGCAGUGCGGAUCGGAGCUCAGCUCAGCGUUCUUGAAGAUCUGGCCUUAUUCCCAGAGCCACAGCCAGUUGAGAACAUGAAAUUGUACCACAGCUGGCUCCUGGUUGGCUCCCGUACUGAGGUGACACAAGUGAAUACAACCAACUGUGGCCGUCUCCAGAGCUGCUCAGAGUGCAUCCUGGCCCAGGACCCAGUCUGUGCCUGGAGCUUCCGGCUGGAUGAGUGUGUGGCCCAUGCCGGGGAGCACCGAGGGUUGGUCCAAGACAUAGAGUCAGCAGAUGUCUCCUCUUUGUGUCCUAAAGAGCCUGGAGGUAAACGUCCUUGGAAAAAAGGGAAUAUGAACCUACAGGAUUCCAGUCAACAAAAUAAGCUGUCCACAUGCUACCUCUACAAAGAGACGGUGUCUCACCAUGUUGCCCAGCCUAGUCCCAAACUCCUGGCCUCAUGUGAUCCUCUCGCCUUGGCCUCCCCAAAGUGUUGGGACUACAGGUGUGAACCACUGUGCCCUGUCUUAUUGAGGGAGUUUAAAGCCUGGUGCUUGAAUGCUGUCAAUAACUGAGGUAACUUACAAGGUACCCAAGUUUACCUUUGAGCUACUCUGACUUCCAAAGGGUCUUCUUUAGGUUCAGCUGAAAUCUGUCUUUUCCAAUUUUCCAAUCAUUAGUCCUCAUGUCACCCCUUGGGGUACACACAGAAUAUCUCCAGCACCUUUCCCAGCUGACCCAGACUAUGGCCCACUUUACUACCAUAAUCCAUCUGAGUCACCUCUGUGGAUCAGAUACCUCCUAGGUUUUCAGCCAUUCUCCACAUGACAUGGCUUCAGGAACUAUCCCCUACACCCACAUGCUGAGUUUGCAAUGCCUCAGGGGGACCUCCAAGUGAAGAUGCCACAUAGGCUGUUGGAUAAAUAAUCUGACAUUCAGAGGGAGGACUAAGAUAAUGGAUAUAGAUUUGAGAAUCAUUAGCUCAUGUUGGGGGUGGUUGAAGGUAGUUGAGGUCACCUAUGGAAACUGUAAGAUUAAGAGAGGAUGGAACCUGGGGGAAGAUAGAUUGUUCAAGGGUAGGUGGAGGAAGAUGGAGGAGCAUACAAGAGACAUGGAGAAGGAGCGGUUGGAGAGGCAGGGGAAUGACCAAGAGAGUGUUACCAUAGAAACUCAGGGAGGAGGGUGUUCAAAAUAGGGAUAGCAGUGAUGUCUAAUAUAGCAGAGGCCCAGGCAUUUGUCAGCUUCUCAGAAGAAGUGAGAAUGAGAACUAGAGAACAUAGGGCUGAGGAGAGAAUGGGAGGGCAGAAGUGGAGGCAGGGAGUGAAGACAACUUUUUGAGCUGCUAGCUGGGAAGGGGAGUCAAAGGAGUGCCAUUUGUGAUUAGGGUGGGAGAGACCCGAGCUUGUUUCAAUGCUAAUGGAAAGAGCCAGGAGGAGGAUGAGGUGGAAGAUAUGAGGAGAGUGGGUGGAAGAUAUGCGGAGAAUGGGAAGAACACCACGGCUGACAUGGUCUUGAGGAAGAGCGUUGGGGGCAUGAAAGGACAGUGGAGGGAAUUAUUCUUAAAUAAUCUGCAGAAAGGACAGAUAAUUCACAGAGGGGGAGGAAAGGCAAUGUGGAUGGGCUUCAGAGCAGACAUCUCUGAAAGAAUGUAGGGGUAGGGUAGAGGGCAAGAUGUCUAGUUUUGCCUUGACGUAGUAGAUGAGGUCAUCUGUUGCCAGUAAAGGGAGCAAUGGUAGAGUAAGGGUCUGAGAAUAAAUGCCACAUGUGGGAAUAGGUUCCCCUGCUCCUCACUAAAUGAUAUGUCUCCUGCCUGACCCUGAGUAGCACCAUGGCUCCUGCUGCCCCCUACCCCAUCCAUGGCAUUGGAUCCAACCAUUGGCCUGAAUGGGACCUCAGUUUAUUAUCUUCAGCCUCGCAGGCUAGAUUGCUGAUUAAUACUCUUGUUGUCCAAACUCUUCUCUUAGAUAAGGCAGAGCCUGGGGGUGUGGGAGGGAUUCUUCCAAGUGCUUUAGAAAAAUCAUUUAUUCCUCAAGCAAUCAUACAAAGUAGGCACUAGUGUUAUCUCCAUAAAAAAACUGAGGCACAGAGAGGGUAAGUAACUUGCUCAAGGUCAUUCAGUUGGAAGAGCAGAGCUAGGAUUCAAAUCUCAGGCACUGGUUCCAGAGACCAUGUUCUUAACUUUCUUUAGUAAAAGAAAGUGAAGGUAACAUGCAGAACAAAGGACAGAAGGAAGGUGAAGAGACAGUUCUAAUGGUGUUUCAGUUCCUGGUUCUUGUGCUUGAGGUCUCUGGAGAAUUCCUGGUUCCUGCUUUCUUGAGGCUUAAUUCUUCAGUUAUUCAUUUGAUGCUGUGAGAUACCCCAGUGUCAUUCUAGUAAAACAUGAAAUUGGAGAGAUUCAGCUGGAGGUUCUGAUGCAUUCCUGGGACACUUAGCCUUCAGUAGCCCCUGAUAUUUGGGGAUCUCUGAUGGGUGGGGUAUGGCUUAGCCAGAGGGGAAUGUGUAGCACCCAGCUGCCUUGCUUGUGGGAGAGGAUGGGGCUGUUGAGGUUACUGAGCUGGAACGGGCAUGGAGGUCUCCAUUGUUCUGACCUUGCCUUUCCUGGAUUGCCCCACAUUCCAUCCUAUUGAGGUGAUCACUGGUUCACUGGCAGAGAUGGGACACUGUUUAUCAGUUCCUUCUGGGUUUCCCUUCCUUCCUUACCCAGCCUGGGACCCACUAGCUUUUUCAGCUACAUUCUCAUCAAUGAAUCCCACCUUUCUCUCCCUGCGCACCUGUCAGUGUCAGGCCAUCUCCCAGUCCUGAAUCAGCCCUACCAUUUAUUUUCUCUAGUCGAACUCAGCUAUAGAAAAUUCCACAGCCAGGUUGAGUGGUUCCAGAACAAAUUUAUGACUUCCAACCUCAGCUGUGUUCACAAUGCUGCUAAAAAAAUCUUUUCAUUCAGUCAGUACUUUUCAGAUACCCCAAGUCCAUUGCUCUGAGCUCUCGCCAUGCUCCGUGAGUCCCUCCCCCAACCUCAGCACCUCUCGUUGUUUGUAGCCUCUAUCUUCACAGCUGGGGGCAGGGGUGAGAUGCAUAUUGACUGAGUAGUUGGUGAAGUGGUACAUGCUGUGCCUAGAGUAUGAAAAGAAAUGAAAUUGGAGGAUUCUCACAUCACACUAUGAAAUCUUUGUCACUUGUUUCAGUUUAGAGAUAUGCAAAGUCACUGAAAAGAAGCAAGUUGGAUCCCAGGUCUGGAGUAUGGCUUUAACCUGUCUAAAAAGAAUGUGUCUAUUUACAAGGGUCUUGGGCAGCCUGGAAGCCCAGGAAAAAGGUAAUCCCAGAGGUCAACCAUUCCAGCCGUUGAGCAAUUGCAAUUGAUCACACAUACACUCAUGGAGUUCCAGUGGGACCCCGAUGAGAAGGGCAUUGUGGUAAACUUGAGCUUCAUAAUGCUGCAGCUGCAGCAAUUUGGGGAACACUGAGAUCUCUCCAUGGCUCUUCCGAGCCUCUCAAAAACAUUUAACACAAUCAUCAGGAUUAGGGACCUGACAGCCAAGAGGUAAGUUUGGCAGCCCUGAGGCAUUUGCUUUUAACAAGCUCCCAUGAUGAUGUCAACUCCCCAAUUUAUAUCUCUAGCCCUCUUGCUUGAACUUCAGACUAUUGACAACUGUUUACAGAACAUCUGCUCUUGAGUGUUGAAGUGACAUCUCAAAUUCAAGAUGACCAAAACUUAACUCCUUCCUCUGCCCUGAAACCUGUUCUAUCUGCAGUCAUCUCCAUUCAGUUCAUGUUUAUGAUACAGCUAAAAUUGCUCAUCAGCAUCUAAUGAAGCAACGAAGCAACUUUGUCAAUCAGACAUUGUUGUUUUACUUUCUUUUUCUUCCAUAAACUUACUCUAUGGUAGUUCUUUUGUUAGUAUGGACUUUGAACUCUUCCUGGGCAUCUCCAGACCUGGUCUCUCAUCAAAAGGCUGAUCUCAUCUAAUUAGGGCCUGAGGACUGCAAGGGAGGGAAGAUCAAGGGGAAUCCUAGAAACCUGGAUUCCGUUCAGGCAGGAAAGCAGAUUGAUGAUCAAUGGCCUGGGUCCAUGCCACUUACUGCUUGUGAGACUAGGAAAGUUAUUUACUUUCCAGACGAUUCAUAGAUCAACCUAGGGGAGGGGGUGUUGAUUAAAUGAGAAUAUGUAUAGUCACUGAUGCAUAGUAAAAGCUCAGUUAACUACUGGUAGUAAUGCUUUAUCUUAGGAUAUUCUGAGCUAGAAAUAAAGUAAAAAAUGAAAUUGAUUUGGGAGCCUAAAGAAAUUAUCCUGAAAUGCAUAAAGAGAAACAUGUAAAAUACUCAUUGAAAAGCUGAAAUGGAAAAUGGUCAUUUUCCCAUAGAUAUUGGUGGUUCACUUCAUAAAUCUUUCUGAAUUAAUCCUUUAAUUCAGUAUGUAUUUAUUGAGCAUUUACUAUAUGUUAGGCUGUUAGGCACUGCUCUAAAUGCUGAAGAAAAAUCCGUGAGCAAAACAGGUGAAAAUCCCUACAUUUCUGAAGCUAACCUUCUAUUGGGGGUCAUAUAUUGAACAAAAUAAAUAAUACUACGGGUUGGAGGAAAGGAGAUGAUUCAUUUGGAGUUUUUAAGUAGAGUGAUCUGGGACCUAACGUCAUCUUCUGAGCUGGGGGAAGAUACAAAAAAAUCUUAAAAUAUAGUCCCAGCCCUCCAGAAAUGCACAUUUUGGUUAAGGAAAUAAGACAGGAUUCACAUGCCAAUUUUGGUGAUAGAACAAACAAGGCAUUAUUAUGUACAUGGAGACAAGCAAUGUUCUAAAAGGUCAGAGAAGCUGGGGAGCAGGAAGGGAUGCAGCCCAAGGACUUGUUGGCAUGAGUGGUCUGGAAAAGUCUCCUGAAGGGAGUGGAACUUAGCCGCGAAAUAGUGAAGCAAGUUUUCUUCCAUCCUUCCUCCCCUCCCGUUAGCUGCUGGGAAGCAGCUUGUGUUGCAAUGGGCCAAAAUGAAACACUAAUCUUGGCCUUUUCCAGGAAGAGGCUGUCAUGGGGAGAUACCGUAACGGGCAUAGAAAAACAAUCACAAUAGCUUCAGUGGAUCCCCACGUGACCUGGCCAAAUUGGCUGGAGAGGGAACAAGUCUUUCAGGUCAAGCUCAGGCUUUGAACUCAGUAGGAACCAACCCCUGCAGAUUCAGUAACACCUUCUACUUCCAAAUCUUUAUAGCAUGAAAAUCCAAGGGGGCCACAGAUUGCUCUGAGUUAACCACCAGGAGCUGCCAAUAGGAGGGUCCUCCUGCAUCUCUUUCUUAAGGCUUUGGGUUUGUACCUGUACUCUAGAGAUGUGGCCAAGCCCCACUUGUGGUCUGUGUUAGAGGAGCCCCAAAGAACACAGACACGAACCUUGGGGGUGGUAGCCAGGUGUAAAGUAGGGCUUGAGAAGAGUGAGUUCCUAGUACCCAUUUUAGAUUAGACUGCACAGGGGAGAAGACAGGCAGGAUGUGUGAAUCAGGAAAUAGAUUGGUUCUUUGGGCCUAAAUGAGUGUCAAAUCUCCAAAGAGUCAAGUACAUUAAAUUCAUCCCAGCUUGGUGAGGUAGGUGCUAAGUUUUUCUAACAAAGUAGAUGUUUGAAUAAUUGGGGCCUUAGAUGAGUCACUAUAGUGGACUGGGUAUGGAGAGGGGCAGCAUUAUUGAUCUCCUUUUCCUCAUUCUCCAUGUAGAAUUGCUACUAGAGUCUUACCUCUAUUUUCUCAUGGCUAUUUGGCCUUCAACUUGAAAUAGUAUCUAGUAUGAUGCAUGGGUUGGAUAAAGAUGUCAGCCCUUGUAAAAUAUUGCAGUUACUUUGAAAAAAGGCUGGAGUUCUCAACUGGGAUCCCUUCUUACCAGCUACGUGGCCUUGAGCAAGUUGAUGCACGUCUCUCAGGCUGUUUUCUUGUCUGUACAAUUGGCUAGUGUAAACUUCAUGAGGUUAUUGUAAGGAUCAAAUUAGAUAAUGCAUGUAGAGUAUAGCACCAAUAAUUGUUUAUUGUUAUUACUUUUAUUAUCUAACCAAUUGGAGAUGAGGAAAAGUAAUUAUUAGGGGACAAAUAUUGUAUAACGAGCCGACACAAGAGUGAGUGGAAACUGUAACUUGCCUACCAAUGCGGGCUGGAUUCACACUUAGCCAGACGUCUCCAAUAAUGCUCCCAGCCCUAGCAGAACCCCAGUUGCCCUCCGAAUGGUCACUGGAUUUGUCCCUUCCUAUCUUCUCUCCUUCUCCAAACCCGGCCCCAUAAUCCUGACCUUCAUUUCUGCUAGCCCUGGAAUCCUAUGAUUUGCCCUGCUCUUCUUCAGCUCCUCCCAACACUGCAGAUGUCUUUGUUCUCCUAUGCGUUUGGUCCUCCUCCUGCCCCUCAAUCCAAGGGUCCAUCAGUUUCAUGCAAAUUAGGAUCAUAUUCUCUUCAUGACCACUCAUCCUAGAAGGGAAAGCUUGCAAAUGUGCAGAUGGGUUUGGUGUGAGGGUCAGGAUGGACAGAGAAGUGCAUUUAUUCAGUCCAACAUUUUCUAAAUACAAAUUACAUUUUUUAAAAAAGGAAAUUAAAAUAACAAUUAAAUACCAUUUCCCCAUGGCAAAGGCAAGCAAAGAAUGACCGUAUACCCUGAGUAGGUGAGGAAUAUAAUUUGGUAACAUCUUUCUGGAGAGCAAUUAGGCAAUGUAUUUCAAAAGUGUUAACAUUUUCACAUUUUCUUUAUCCUAGCAAUUCCACUCUUAGGAAUUUAAUUGAGAAUAAGAACAAAGAUUUACAAGCUUGUCAUCACAGUAAUUGCCUGGAAAUAGUGAAAAAAUUGCAAAAGAUCUAAGUAUUCAAAAAUAAGGAAUUGGUUGAGUAAGUAGAGACAUCCCUGUAUAGGUUUACUCUGUAGCCAUAAUGGAUAAUAUUGAGAAAUCUAUUUAUGGUCAAUGAAAGAUGUUUGUCAUAUAUUAUCAUAUAAAAAGCAGAUUAUAAAGCACUAUGUACAGUAUUUUACAAUGAGUAUUUAAAAACUUUUUAUAGAAACAGGGUCUUGCUCUAUCACUCAGGCUAGAGUGCAGUGGCACAAUCAUAGCUCACUGACGCCUCUGACUCAUGGGAUCUGGUGAUCCUCCUGCCUCAGCCUCCUGAGUAGCUAGGACUACAGAUGUGUGCCACCAUGCCUAGCUAAUUUUUAAUUUUUUUUGUAGAGAUGGGAUCUUGCUAUUAUUGUCCAGGCUGGUCUUGAACUGCUGGUCUCAGGCAAUCCUCCUGCCUCAGCCUCUCAAAAGCACUGGGAUUAUAGGUGUGAGCCACUGGGCCUGGCCAUAUUUGCACAUUUUUAAAGUUUCAAAAGAUAUGUAUCAAUUUAUACACUAGUAUCUUGGUGUUUGGAGGUUACAAGUUAUUCUCUAUUUUCUUUUCUUUUUUUUUGUAUAUUUUCUGAUUCCUUUAUGGUUAAUGUGAAUUAGUCAUGUAAUUACAAGCCAUUUUAAUUUGCAUUAAAUUACUAGUAACACAUUUUAGGCUUUGGGAAUUCAAAAAAUGAAUAAGAGAAGGAGAAACAACAUUUAUUGAAUUUUUUUUAACAUUUUAGGCAAUGAGCUGAAUCCUUUGUAUAAUUUAAUUCAUUUAAUUUUUACCAUAAUUGCAUGGGAUAUUAUGUUUCCAGUUUACAGAUAAGGGAACUGAGGCUCAUAGAAGAUUAGAAACUAGCCUAAGAUUGUACAUUCAGUGGGAUUUGAAACCAGAUCUGACGCCAAAGAACUUAUCGAUAUUCAUACAGGUUUAAAAUUUUUCCAUGACACCACAGGAGCUUGCAGUAUUAGAGGGGCUCAGAACCCACAAACCCAAAGACUUCAGGUCCAGGCAGACCCAGAUCAGUGGCUCAUGAGUGAGACAAACAUAGGGUCAUGGAGAUGCAUAGAGGGGAGAUCUGGCUGCAUAAUCAGGGAGUGAGAUCUGAUGUGAACUUGAUGUCAGAUUUCAGGAAUCAGCAAUUGAGGCUAGAGCUUUUCCCGAAGGCCAAAGAAUGUGGGUGCAGUGGCAAGGAGGAAGAGUAGGGACAGAUGGGUUGUCUGGAGUAGACGUGGGGAAGUUUCUGACACAGGCAGUACUGGACAAGGUUGUCUGCACGAGGUUUGUUGAUUCAUAUUUCACGGUUAAUCUCUUUGCAUUUAUUUAUUUUAUAGCAUUACCACUUUUGUGUCAUUGAUUUUCACUUCUGAGUUUGCCUAUUUGUUUGAAAUCUCUUCAUCUCAUUUCUAUUAGUUUUUAUACUCCAUUGAGCACUUCUCAGUGAGUGAGCAUUUUCACUUCACACUCAUCAAAGAGCCAAAUGAGGAGAGGAGACACCCUAACUGCAGGGAUUAGGUAGUAGGCUUCAGAGGCAGUGACCAAGCAGGAUCCCUGGUAGGCCACUCCCUCUCCUCUGCUACCUGGAAGCAGAACAAGGCUGGAUCUCACCCUUCUGCUACCUGCAUUUAACUAACUAGGAAGUCAUAUGGGUUAUAUUUUAAAAUAUAUUUUAAAAAUAUGUAUCUGACAAAUGCAUUUCAUGAUCCUAGAUUGGAUUCUGGGUUGGAAAAAAUUACUAUAAAGUACAUUGGCAAAAUUUGAAUGUAGGCUAUAUAUUGUAUAAUAGUUUGUUAUCAAUGCUAAAUUUUCCAAAUUUGUUAAUUAUACUGUAGUUAUAUAAAAAGAUCCUUGUUCUUAAAAGACAGAUGCUGAAGUAUUUGGGGUUAAGGAGCAUGAUGUCAGCAACCUAUUCUUAAAUGGCUAGGCAAAACCAAUAAUAAUGUGUGCAUGUGUGCAGAUUAUCUAUUUAUCUAUCUAUCCAUCUAUCCAACUAUCUAGAGAGAAAUAAAACAAAUGAGGCAAAA